ACGUUUCAGAGAGGCUGCAGCCCGGCGCAGCAUCCUGAGCGCGCCUCUGCCGAGGCGAGCGGACAUGCAGGCUCCCCGCGCAGCCCUAGUCUUCGCCCUGGUGAUCGCGCUCGUUCCCGUCGGCCGGGGUAAUUAUGAGGAAUUAGAAAACUCAGGAGAUACAACUGUGGAAUCUGAAAGACCAAAUAAAGUGACUAUUCCAAGCACAUUUGCUGCAGUGACCAUCAAAGAAACAUUAAAUGCAAAUAUAAAUUCUACCAACUUUGCUCCGGAUGAAAAUCAGUUAGAGUUUAUACUGAUGGUGUUAAUCCCAUUGAUUUUAUUGGUCCUCUUACUUUUAUCCGUGGUAUUCCUUGCAACAUACUAUAAAAGAAAAAGAACUAAACAAGAACCUUCUAGCCAAGGAUCUCAGAGUGCUUUACAGACAUAUGAACUGGGAAGUGAAAACGUGAAAGUCCCUAUUUUUGAGGAAGAUACACCCUCUGUUAUGGAAAUUGAAAUGGAAGAGCUUGAUAAAUGGAUGAACAGCAUGAAUAGAAAUGCCGACUUUGAAUGUUUACCUACCUUGAAGGAAGAGAAGGAAUCAAAUCACAACCCAAGUGACAGUGAAUCCUAAACCUGAAUGGCGCUCAUGUUUUCCAAGAGAAGCAGCCCCUGAGGGAGUCUGCUGAGGCUGCCAACAGAGGAUGAAGAGGAUACAAAUUUAAUUAAUUUCAAAUCAACAUAGACACAAGAACCUUUUGCUGUUUCUUCCAACGCCCACUCUUCCUAAUGAUGGCAUCACUUGCACUUGGAAGAAUGUGCAAUUGAGAAGUACUAGGAAAAGGCCUGGCUGCCAUCCAUCGCUGCCUCUGAGGGUGGAGAAGGAGGCGGGUGAUGUGCUCACUUCUGAUCAACAUGUGUUGCCUCCUCUCAGCCAACUUCUAGCUCACUGAACUCACUCUGGUCAUGAUAAAUGUUCGUCACCUUUCUGCUUCAUUCCUUAGGGCCUAAAUCAGGAAGCUGUUUUAUCGAUGGUUUCCUUUUGGGUCAGUAACCAGCUUUGGAUAAUUUCCUCUGAUUAUUCAAGUCGUGGGACAGGUAAACUACAUUCAGCAGGAACUUUUCUCGAGGAGUGUUAUGUCAUGGAAAAGACACCAAACACAGCAAGUAUUUUAAUGAAUACACCAUCCCAGGGGGUCAGUAAGCUCUGCCUGCCAAGAAGACACAGUGAGAGGGGUCCACAGUCCUGAUGAGGUGGCGUUUGGUAACUUGUAGACCCUAGCAUGGCCAGGUCUGGUCACCCUUAAGAACUUCUCAGAGAAACUAGGAAUCUUCAGUGAAAGAACUAAUGUUCUCCUCAGCUGAAAUUCCCUUGCUUGUCAGCAUUUCUGCAAAGCUCACACUUGUUUCACCAUACCUCCCUUGGAUGUGACAUGUAGGUAGGAAGUAUGUGCAGGUGGGAGUCAUCUGUCAGCCUUCUAUGUUUCAGAGAUCCUGAAGGUGGUUUGAAACAAACAGAAGAGGAGCAGGAAAUAUCCGUGCCUGUGGCAGAUCUCACUCAUCAUGCUUAGCAUUCUCUCCCGCCAAGCUGGGAUAAGCCUCAUGUCCUAACACAGCACAACAGGAGGUCUCUGUCAGUCCAUCAGAGAUGACAUUCUAUGUGAUAUUUUUGACAUCCUUGUGCUAAAAGCAAUGGCACAAAAUGGAAAAGGGCCUAUUGACCACACCUACUCCAGUAAAAUUGUUCUUCAUUUAUUCCUUAAUUUUCUAAAUCUGACCCCUUUAAAGCAAUCUAGCAAAUUGAGAAUCCUCAGCUCUCCUUGGAUACCUGAUAUUUUAUUUCAAGAAAGAGACAAAGAAGGAAAAUUUUAUUUAUUUUACUACCCACAUAUAAACCGAAGGGAGAUGGGACUACCCAAACAUUUGCUGCUCAAUUUUGUGUCUUGUGCUUGAAAGUCUGCCCUAAUGCAUAACAAAAACUACUUGUCUCCUACCUUUUGGGAUCCCUUUAACAAGUAUUUGCCUUCUGAACUACGUGGAUAAUUUCAAAGGCAGAGUUCCAGACCAGAGAGGUCUUUCCAUACAAUGAAAGCUAUAACUAGCUGGUUGUGUUUAACCACUGCUAUCACGCUAUCCUGGGACUGCAUAGAACUUUGACAAAAGACAGACUUCAUGGUACACAACUUCAACAGAUUUUCUGUCAUAUUCUCACCAGCACAUCUGAAUGAGGCUUUGUGUUUUCCUUGCUCUCUUGCAUGUUCCUUUUCAACUCAUGGCCCACAGUGACUCUCAGAUAUUUAUGCCAAAAUUGCAUACAAUUGUUUUCUGAAUCAUAACUUGUCUAUUUUUCUGCCUAUGUGUGCUACUUUCAGUUUGUUUCUCAUCAACAUUUUGACUCUCAGAAGAGCCUCCAUUUGCCCCUUUCUCUCUUUAGGUAUCUAAGAUCUUUGAACACCUGGGCCUUUACAUUUGAUCCAACCCUAUCAAAUAAUGAACUUCUCAGAGAGGCAUCUGGGGUCCUGGAACUUCAUGUUGAUGAAGUCAUAUUAUAUAAUAUGAUAAAAAUAUUCUCAUGCAGUAUUUUAAAUAAUUUCAAAUUCUAGAAGAAGCAAAUUUCAGCGACAUGUCAUUGAGUUUUUAUUUGGUAAAGCUAUAAUUGUGCAGUGUACAAAGCACUUUUUAAAAAGAUAGUUUAUUCUGUCAGGGUAUAUGAAGUUAGUAUACAGCCAGAACAGCCAAGCCUCAAUUCUUGUACCUUGUGUCUUUUUAUUACUGUUUAAUCAAUAGAUAUCAUAUGUUUAUGACAGUUUCAAGAAUUGUUUUUAAACCCAAACUUAAUUUUAUGUUUCAGACUAUUGUUAAAAAAACAAAACAAAAACCAAAAAAACCCUCACUAAUUUGCCCUAAUUGGAUAGGGCAAUCAGAACAAAAUCUGACUUUCGAAUAUUUAAAAGAUAUGUAAGUUUGAUUGCAUUUUCGUACAUUUUAAGCAAACUAGGUUAACAACAACAUAGCCUAGUCAAACUUCUCAGGAAACUUGUUUUAAUAAAUAUGUAAAAAUACCCAUUCAUGACUCUUGACCCAAUGGUGUGACUCCUCCCUCUGGGAAGGGCUUUGUUACCCAAUGCAAGACCACAGCCUGGAUCCACCUUGAUGUAGGUGGCUCCUGGAUAACCCACAUCAAACAAAUGUGAUAAAGAUGAGUAAAACUGGUCUUGGGAAAAUAAUUUCAUAGUUUUUUUUUCUCCUAGUUAUGCUGUAUAAUACAGGAGAACCAAAAGCUGUAAAAUUAUUUUAUUUUAUUUUUUAAAGACAGGGUCUCACUAUGUUGCCCAGGCUGGUUUCAAACUCCUGGGCUCAAGCAGUCCUCCUGUCUCAGCCUCCCAAAGUGCUGGGAUUACAGGCAUGAGCCACUGAGCCCGACCAGCUGUAAAAUUAUUAUAUUCAUUUUCACUAUGUGCUACUUCUUCUCACCUGACUUUUUUUUUUUUUUUUUGAGAUGGAGUCUCACUCUGUCACCCAGGUUAGAGUGCAGUGUCACGAUCUCGGCUCACUGCAACCUCCGCCUCCCAGGUUCAAGCAAUUCUCUUGCCUCAGCCUCCCAAGCAACUGAGAUUACAGGCCUGUGUCACUAUGCCCAGCUAAUUUUUGUAUUUUUAGUAGAGAUGGGGUUUUCACCAUGUUGGUCAGGCUGGUCUCAAACUCCUGACCUCAAGUGAUCCACCAGCCUCGGCCUCCCAAAGUGCUGGAUUACAAUUGUGAGCCACUGUGUCUGGCCACACACUGACUUUCACUGUAAUAUCUGGAUGUUUUAUGUAACAUAUCUGGGCAAUAGGGCUUAUGGCAGAAUUGGCCCUCGUGGUGUAGGCCUUCCAAGUUCCAAGUCUCAUUUUUAGUAUUCCUCCGUUCCAACCCCUGGAUCCACCAGUUCCAACAGCCUGGAUCCACCUUGAUAUUGACAGCCAGGCAGAUGCUUCUGCUGAUCACCGCAGCUCUAGCAAUGGAAAUGGAUAUGUUAAGAAAAUACUUGUCUAUUCUUUUAUUUUGGUGGUUUAAACUAUUAAUUCACACCAUCUCUGAAAAAAGGCCUUAUGUUGACUAAAGAAAACAUAGGCUUUAGUUUCAGCUUCUGUCAGAAUUAGUACCAAUUCUGAAUCUGGUGGAGUGAUAAGACAUGGUUUCAUGCUGGGAAGACACUGCUGAAAUCCUCCUUGUGGGAGAACAUGGAAAUUUUAUACUGAAUUAAAUUAACGCAUGUGACUUUUCACAUUCAGAGACAUUCAGGAUGAAUUCUGGGGUUUCCAUUUAAUAGCUAUAACAGGCAGUCCAGAACAACUUCACAUAUAGCAGCAUUUCUGCUAUGUGACAAUGACCAAAAGAGUUCCUGUAUAUUAGUGUCUAGUGGAAUAUUUCAAAUUGCAGAACCCAGACAACCAAUUGCCUGAAUUAUUAUUAUUUUUUGUUUUUAGCAACUCUUUGGCUUUAUCUUGAUACUGUCUUGUCUGGCACCAAAGUUUUAUUUCCUUCUUAGUCCUCUUGGGGAUAGUUUUUGGGUGUUUUUUUUUAUUUUUCUUUUUUUGAGACGGGGUCUCAUGCUGAUGCCCAGGCUGGAGUGCAAUGGUGUGAUUAUGGCUCACUGCAGCCUCAACUUCCCAGGCUCAGGUGAUUCUAUUACCUCAGCCUCCCAAGUAGCUGGGACUACUGGUGUGCACUACUAGGACUGGCUAAUUUUUUGUAUCUUUUGUACAGAUAGGGUUUCACCGUGUUGCUCAGGCUGGUUUUGAACUUCUAGGUUCAAGCAAUCCUCCCACCACAGCCUCCAAAAGUCCUGGGAUUACAGGUGUGAGCCACCAUAACUGGCUGGAAUUAUUUGUACCUGGACCUUGUGUUUUGUUUUUUUGCCCUACUAUCUUUUCUAAAUAACAUAUCAUGUUCCUGAGAUAGCAGUAUAUACAAUUAUGUAAAAUAGAGCUUUAUAUGAACUCUGUACAUGCUCUAAGCUCUUUUUGAAUGAUAUUUUAAGAAGUUUCUAAACCAAAGUGCUUAAGAAAACAUGAAGAUGUUAAUUUCAUGAAGACUGUACAAGUUUAGAAGUACAAUGUAGACCUGUUUAAGACAAAGGUGGAUGGGCUUUGGGGUUUUUUUUACAAUUGGACUUCAGGUACAGAAGGCUUGGGUAAUGGUACUCCUCAGUUCAUAUCACCUUAUCAUUGGCCUUUAGUAUUUUGUAAAUAAGUAACUGGACUUUUAUGAAAAGCAUAUUCUUAACAGUUUCCCAUUUCCUUUUUUUUUUUUUUUAAGAUAGUGUUUUGCUCUGUUGCCCUGGCUGGAGUGCAGUGGCAUGAUCUUGGCUCACUGCAGCCUCCACCUCCCAGGCUCAGGCGAUCCUCCUGCCCCAGCCUCCCAAGUAGCUGGGAUUACAGGCGUGCACAACUGCAUGCACAACUAAUUUUUGUAUUUUUAGUAGAGACAGGGUUUCGCCAUGUUGGCCAAGCUAGUCUCAAACUCCUGGGCUCAAGUGAUCCGCCCACCUCAGCCUCCCAACAUGUUGGGAUUAUAGGCAUAAGCCACCAUGCCCAGCCAGUUUUCAUUUCUUUGGUCUGCAUGUAAAGGACUAAAGAAUGAUAUGUAGCUACUACACUGCAGCAAACAACAUUUUUCCAGUGUACAAAUCAGUGGAGAGUAAGCAAUGUAUUACUCUGAUGUCGGUGAAACACCUCAAAUUAUAAAUAAUGCCAGGAACAUGUGAAAACUCCACAUGUUUAAUAAAUGCCAGCUUUCAGAAAAAGCAGAGAUUAUAGGUAUUCAACAAGUUAAACAAUAAUCUGGUAGAUUAGUAAUAAUUUAACACAUGUGUAUCUUGUAUUUAAAGUUAACUGAAAAUUAUGUAAAAAAAAAAAACACUGUGUUUGACUUUCUUUUGUUUUACAAGUGAUGCAGAGUAUCUGCUGAGAAGGUCAGUUAGAUCAUCUGAUGUCAUAUUUGCCACUUAGCUUUUGUCCCAGCAGCAUAUAAAUUCUACCUUGUAAGCCUCAUAUUAGAAGUGGUCCCAGCCAGGCACAGUGGCUUACUUCCCAACACUUUGGGAGUCCACGGCUGGUGGAUUGCCUGAGCUCGGGAGUUUGAGACCAGCCUGGCCAACAUGGUGAAACCCCAUUUUUACAAAAAUGCAAAAAUUAGCCAGGUGUGGUAGUACACACCUGUAAUCCCACCUACUCGGGGGGCUGAGGCCCAAGAAUCACUUGAACCCAGGAGGCGGCAGUUGCAGUGAGCCAAGAUUGUGCCACUGCACUGCAUCCUGGGUGACAGAGCAAGAUUCUGUCUCAAAGAAAAGAAAAAGAAAUGGUCCCAUUGCUACGGAUUAGAACUAAUUUGUAAAACUAUCAGAAUUUUAAGACUGAUUAAAGGUUUUAGGUGUUUUUCUCCUACUUUGCAUACUGAGAAUAAUAUGUAUAGUAUUUUUCCAGUAUGAUUUACAAUUUUAUAAAUGUCAGUAUACAUAUGUAUAUAUAAAUUAUUCUCAACUCCAUUUUUUUUUAAAUAAAAUAAGUACAUGUUUGUGUGCUAAAUUGCUCAUUUGGCAGUGAUAGAUUGAAAAACAUUUAUAAAUUUAAAAAUAAAGCACUAUAAGAUAUGAGGAAUGAAUAGCUUCUAUGUGAAUUUCUAUGUAAUUAAUAUCAAUAUUUAGAAUAAAAGUGUAUUUGAGGAUAAGAUAUUUGUUUACUAAAAUGUUUUAUUUACUAAGAGUAGAGGUGAAUUAUGCAUCUUUCUAAGGAAAAGUUCUUUUAAUUUCUGUGUCUAUGAAAAAGAAUUCAUAAUUCAUAAUUCUUAAUUGCCCUCUUUUGAUCCAUAUAAUUCUUUAAAUAAACGAAACAAUACCAAUUCAAAAAGGGGCCUGCUUUGUAUAAAAUUGUCUAACCUAAAAAUUAAGUAGACUUUCUGCAUAUCUAAAAUAUAUUAUUACACAUUCUUGUCUUUAUUCUUCCUUACAAAACAUUUUUAAAUGAAGGAAUGAAAUUUUAAUUGUUUAUGAGAAUAUAACUUUUAAAAAUAUUUCUAGUAGGCCAGGCAUGGUGGCUCAUGCCUGUAAUCCCAGCACUUUGGGAGGCUGAGGCACGUGGAUCACCUGAGGUCAGGAGUUCGAGACCAGUCUGACCAAUAUGGUGAAACCCUGUCUCUACUAAAAAUACAAAAAUUAGCCAGGCAUGGUGGCUGUCGCCUGUAAUCCCAGCUAUUCGGGAGGCUGAGGCAGGAGAAUUGCUUGAACCUGGGAGGCGGGGUUUGCAGUGAGUGCCAAGACUGAGCCACUGCACUGCAGGCUGGGUGACAGAGUGAAACUCCAUCUCAAAAAAAAAAAAAAUUCUAGUAAAAAUGGAAAAAUCCACAAGAAAACCUCUUUUUUUCCUGAUUACUCACUUUUCUUCAUGCCUUUAAUUUUAACCUCAUCUCACACCUUGAUAUUAGAAGAAAGUAAGGCUGAAAGGCAGAUUCAUAAGUUGUAGAUAACAUGAAGACUUCCUUGAAUAAGGAUUUAUUCUUUCGGCUCACAAAGACCAGUCAGUAUUAUUGACAAACAACAGGCAGGAAGAUUUCUCCUAAAAGUCUCAACUAAAGUUAAACCUGGUCCAUUAUGGCAUCAAUCUACCCCUAGAAACUGAUGCAGAGUCUAUUUCCUCCCUGUUUUAACUAGAACUUAGCCAGACUGGAGACAGCAUGGACCCAAAGAGCAUGCAGUCCCACAGAGUUAGGGAAAGGAUGCAUCUUGACCAGCAUUCAUCAUGUGGAUCAGUUAGGAAUUAAGUUCCUGAUUCAAGGUGAGCUCAUAUGGCCGCUCCCUGGUCAUCUAGGACACAAGUUCCUUCUAACUCUUCCCCACCUUCAUUAGUACAGGGCUUCUUUCCUGUGUUGCCACAUGAUCCAAAAUGGUGGUUGUAACUCCAGCAUGAUAUUCACAAGAAGGAAAGAGAGGGAACCAGCACAAGGGUGAGCCUCCCAAGUAGGUCAGCCACUUUUAAAUAGCUUUCCUGCCAGCCCAGUGAAGCAACUCUGCUUACAUCUCAUUGGCCAAUCUCUGCAAGGCAGCAGGGAACAGUCAUCUCUAUGGUUGGUACAUUAUCACUUUCAACAAUAAGGGAUUCUGUCUCACAAAGUGGUGGAAGAAUAUUGGGUAUCUGAAGAGGUAGCCACCCUGGCCAGAAGGUGCUAAACACUAAACAUACAUCAUCUCAUUUUAAUCCUAGUAAUUACUUAUGAGGUAGGUUUAGAGAACUUAUACCUUGUUCCAUGUCUUUCCAACUCCAAAGCACAAGUUUUUAAUCACUGCACUGCACUGCAUCCCCAAUAACUAGCCGUAGGAAAGUGUUUUAAAAGGCAUCACUUGGCGGGGUGCAGUGGCUCACACCUGUAAUCCCACCACUUUGGGAGGCCGAGGCAGGCGGAUCACCUGAGGUCAGGAGUUUGAGACCAGCCUGGCCAACAUGGUGAAACCCCCGUCUCAACUAAAAAUACAAAAAUUAGCCAGGCAUAGUGGCAUGUACCUGUAAUCCCAGCUACUCAGGAGGCUGAGGCAGGAGAAUCACUUGAACCUGGGAGGCGGAGGUUACAGUGAGAUGAGAUCACACCAUUGUACUCCAGCCUUGUCUAAAAAAAAACAACAAAAAAACAAACAAAAAAAAGUUUCAGUCAUUGUCAAGGAUGCCUUAAGGUGAGCAUAGCCUGAGAUAAGAAGUAACAGAGGCUGCAGGCUGAGAUAAGAAGGAACAGAGGCAGUGAAGGCAGGACCCUAGGCCCAGAAGUAAUGGUCUAUCAUGCUGAGAAAAAAGCCAGGGCUUAGAAUAGGGGUGAUAAGUAAAAAGCCUAGUUUUAAAAUCUAAGUGCUGGUAAAGGUUUGGUCACUAGGUGAAAAAAUAAAGUUCCCACUUACUAGAGCUGACAUAAACAGCAUAUGAUCCUCUUUAAGGUUGCAGUGGAGAGGCAUGUCCAGGGACUCUCAAGUUAGAGACAGGUGUGUUUAGUGCUAGAAUUGGAAAGACAUUCAAGCAGACUGGCAUGUUGCCUCUUCACAGCCAUAGUCGUGCUGGCUUGCAGGAUACUCCAGCCUAGAAUGUAUAUAGGAGUGUGGAGAACAGCAAAAUCAGCAUUGCUUGGGAUUCAGCCUGAGCUCAAGUGGCCCACCCCUGGAGGCAUCCAGUGUUCACACUUCCCAAGAGAGAAAACCUGAUUGGAUGGGUGUUUCAGCAGUCUAUUGCUGCUUAAACACCUCAAAACUUAGCAGCUUAAAACAACAACACUCAAUUUAUUUUUCACACAAAUCUGCAAUUUGCAUGAGGCUCAGUGCAAAUGGUUCAACUCUCUCCCACACGGCAUUGGCUGGGCAGUUCAACUGGAUCUGGGGGUCCCACUUUCAGAUGACUCACAUGGCUGGCAAGUUUGUUCUGGCUGUCGGAUAGGAGCCCAGCCAAGCCUGUGGUCCAGCGGCCUUGGCUUUUAUGAUGUGGGCCUCUCCAUAGACUCCUUGGGCUUCUUCACAGCAUGGCAGCUGAGUUCCAAGAGCAAGUGUCCCAAGAGAGCAAAGUAGAAAUGCAUAGUAUUUUUAUAAUUUAGACUCAGAAAUCACAUCACAUCACUUCUGCCAUACUUUAUUGUUUGAGACAGUUACAAAGUCUACCUAGGUUCAAGGUGGAAAGGACAUAAACCCCACUUGUCCUUGGAGGCGUGUCAAAGCCACAUUAUGAGAAGAGCAAGUGGGAUAAGGGAUUUGUUGCAGGCACCGUUGGAAAAUGUGAUCUGCCCAAAUUGGUGUGUCUUCAUGCAAUAUCGAGGAAAUAUAUUAGGUAGUUUCGUGUCAAGGAACAUUGUGGAUAUUUGACCUCCCUGAAUCCCAGUGCCUAUGUGCUCUUUGGCUUGGACAUAGACCCCUGGUCCAGUAGUCUGUAGUAGGUGGUAGAACUAGUUUUACCAACUACAUGAGUCAUGAGCCAUGGGACUGAAUGGGUUGUAGGUGGAUCAGACACAUAGAAAUGUAUGACUACUCUCAAAGCAUGAGGUUAAAAUGGGAGCAGAUUAGACUGAGCACCUUGAGGAUAGGGAUCAGUCUUACUCAUCUCUGUAUCCUGAAAAGUGCUUGGCGCUACUGCACGCUCCAUAAUAACAGAAAAACCAAUUAUUUAAUGAGCUAGGAGUUACAUAUCAUCUUUCCUUAAGUACCUAAUCAGUCUUUAUCAUCAGUGAGUGCAGAACUCAAAUAUGGUAUUGUUCAUCUUCCAUCACCAUUUUCUCCCAAGUUUCCUGGUUUAAUUGCAUUUUCCUCACUUUCCAUCUAAUGGAUCCUGAUGUCAUUCUUUAUCUUUAUUUCAUAUUGUCCUAUUGUGUGUAUUGUAUUGUAUUUUUAGCUACAUUAAAUCCAAUAUGGAAGGAAGCAGAGAACGAUCAUAAUUGAACUAACAAGCAAGUGGAGGUGGAGAGAAAGUGGCCCCAAUUUGGAAGGUGAAGGAAAACUGGGGAUGGAGCCUAACUGAUCAUUAAAAUGCUCGAAGCAGCUCUUUCCAACCCA